AGUUGGAGAGCUGGAGGGCGGAGACAGAACUUCGCGGGAAACUAGAGUAUCUAACAAUAGAAACUCCGGAGGGCUGAUGGGGCCGGGCCUAGAAUUUGGGAAUAAAUUAGUGGGCCGGGAGAGGCUCUGGAGCCGGGUAGAACCAGGGGGAGUGAGUGGAGGGAUAGUUCCAUUAGGGCACUGGGAGUGACGGUAUAACAUAAAGAUCGACGCGGGUGGGGCAAGGCUAGAACGUCCCCAGCAGAACUGGAGAGGCGUAAUCGACCGAGGGCCGGUGCGGUGAGAAAGACCUAAUAGGAGCAGGAAUAGAACGUACUGAUAGAGAGGGCGGGGAUACGACUGUCAGGAUAUACGCCUCACGAGGACAGAAUGAAAGGAAAAACGGGCCAAGGCAGGACUUUGGGAAAGGACUUGUGGGCAGGGAUAGAACGUUCAGUUAGUGGGGUGGAGGUAGAACGUGGACAACGGACAGACUGGAAGUACCGCCGGCCGGAACCCAGCAGAACAUGGACACGAAUCUGAAUGGACGGGGCCUGGAGACUUGGUCCUCUUGGGGCCUGCGGUGCAUGCAGUGUAAGACCAACGGGGAUUGCCGUGUGGAAGAGUGCGCCCUGGGACAGGACCUCUGCAGGACCACGAUCGUGCGCUUGUGGGAAGAAGGAGAAGAGCUGGAGCUGGUGGAGAAAAGCUGUACCCACUCAGAGAAGACCAACAGGACCCUGAGCUAUCGGACUGGCUUGAAGAUCACCAGCCUUACCGAGGUUGUGUGUGGGUUAGACUUGUGCAACCAGGGCAACUCUGGCCGGGCUGUCACCUAUUCCCGAAGCCGUUACCUCGAAUGCAUUUCCUGUGGCUCAUCAGACAUGAGCUGUGAGAGGGGCCGGCACCAGAGCCUGCAGUGCCGCAGCCCUGAAGAACAGUGCCUGGAUGUGGUGACCCACUGGAUCCAGGAAGGUGAAGAAGGGCGUCCAAAGGAUGACCGCCACCUCCGUGGCUGUGGCUACCUUCCCGGCUGCCCGGGCUCCAAUGGUUUCCACAACAACGACACCUUCCACUUCCUGAAAUGCUGCAACACCACCAAAUGCAACGAGGGCCCAAUCCUGGAGCUUGAAAAUCUGCCGCAGAAUGGCCGCCAGUGUUACAGCUGCAAGGGGAACAGCACCCAUGGAUGCUCCUCUGAAGAGACUUUCCUCAUUGACUGCCGAGGCCCCAUGAAUCAAUGUCUGGUAGCCACCGGCACUCACGAACCGAAAAACCAAAGCUAUAUGGUAAGAGGCUGUGCAACCGCCUCAAUGUGCCAACAUGCCCACCUGGGUGACGCCUUCAGCAUGAACCACAUUGAUGUCUCCUGCUGUACUAAAAGUGGCUGUAACCACCCAGACCUGGAUGUCCAGUACCGCAGUGGGGCUGCUCCUCAGCCUGGCCCUGCCCAUCUCAGCCUCACCAUCACCCUGCUAAUGACUGCCAGACUGUGGGGAGGCACUCUCCUCUGGACCUAAACCUGAAAUCCCCCUCUCUGCCCUGGCUGGAUCCGGGGGACCCCUUUGCCCUUCCCUCGGCUCCCAGCCCUACAGACUUGCUGUGUGACCUCAGGCCAGUGUGCCGACCUCUCUGGGCCUCAGUUUUCCCAGCUAUGAAAACAGCUAUCUCACAAAGUUGUGUGAAGCAGAAGAGAAAAGCUGGAGGAAGGCCGUGGGCCAAUGGGAGAGCUCUUGUUAUUAUUAAUAUUGUUGCCGCUGUUGUGUUGUUGUUAUUAAUUAAUAUUCAUAUUAUUUAUUUUAUACUUACAUAAAGAUUUUGUACCAGUGGACAAGGCCAGAACGCUCACUCUGGGGAAGCUGGUUGCCAUGUAAAAGUACUACUGCCCUGAGACCACCAUGCUGUGAGGAAGCCCAAGCUACUCAUGUAUAAAUGCCAUGUGGAGAUAGAGCCCCAGAUGUUUCAGCCAUCUCAGCCCAGGCACCAGACAAGUGGGUGAAGAAGCCACCUUGGACAUGUAGCCCCAGCAGAUGUGAUAUAGAGAAGAAACAGGAAACUUGGCUAUAUUAGUUUCCUAGGGCUGCCUGUGAUAAAUUAUUACAAACUUUAUAAACUAACACAUUGUGUGCCUAUAUCAAAACAUCAUGGAAGGACAGGCACAGUGGCUCAUGCCUGUAGUCCUAGCACUUUGGGAGGGUGAGAAAGGAAGAUCUCUUGAGCUCAGGAGUUCAAGAUCAGCCUGGGCAACACAGUGAGACCUCAUCUCCACUAAAAAUAAAAAAAAAUUGGCUGGA